AUCUUUUGCAACUGCACAGACAUUUGCUACGGGCAGCUGAUCGCUGGGUCCCAGCGCCGCUGGUUUCACAAUUUCGCGGGUGCCCCCCACCAUCCCCAGCCCGCAGCAUAAUCGGUGAAGGGAGCCUGCGGUUUCUCCGCCGCGCCUUCGCCCGUUGCGUCCUGCGAAGCCAGUGGAAUCGGUGGUCACAAGGAAAUUAUGACAGGAGCAACCUGCAGGGGUUUAGAUCUGACAGAAAUAUUCUAAUGGUAGGCAUUGCAUCGCUUAGCCAUAUUUGUAAUUUCUUCUUUGUAGGGUUGGUUCUCUGUAACUUUUGCUUACCUUAAAAUUAUUUUUGUGUCUUGCUCUGAGGACAAUGUUACCGAUGUGUUUUUCAUUUUUACUUGCAUUUCAGACUUUCAUUAUUUUAAAUUAUGUAUUUUUUUUUUCUUCUAAUUUUGAGCGUCUCAGAUUCGUGCUUCUUGACUUUCAUUCUCUCAGGAGCCGGGGAGCCGAGCUCGGUCUUAGCCUCGCUGGUAUCAGGUUCCGGGUUCUGUCUGGAGGCUCCGCUUCCUAUGCAGAGCUGGCGGUUUUGUAUCAGCACGUUUGCCAGUGGCGCCCACUGGGCGUUUUCUCAGUUGCUGCACCCAACGUGACAUUUCCCGUUCGCGGGGUCCUUAGGUUCUCAGUGCUGUCACUUUUUCGCUCCUACAACCGCUAGUAUCUCCUAGGAACUUCCUGAACCCCGUUUUGCCGUGCAGAACGGUGAUUGCACCGAGCCGCUGUUCGCACUAGUAAUUGUGUGGUACCAUUAGCCGGCGCUUUUUCUGUCACAACCCAUUAAAACGGGUUAAAACAUAUUAAACCUAUCAAACACAUUGAACGGAUUAAAACACAUUAAAUGCCGCAACACAUUUUUCUGGUACAACACAUUGAAACAGAGUUGGUUCAUUCCUCCAAACAGGUUGUUUAGGUGUGGAAGCACCGCUCUUAGUUCUAAGAGCAUGCUGUUUCUCUUUAGCAGCACCCUUUACGGCGCCAAAACGGAUAUUUGUUUGGCAAUACCAGCGCUAUCCGCUAGGUGCCGGCGCUUGCUAAGUUCAACGCGCCAGUUUCUCGUUUGCAAGGUGGUUAGGGCAGAGCCCUAGCAGACAGUUUUCCGGUGGCAGCAACGCUCAUUUCCCGGAAACGGGUGGUUCUUGGCCCUUGCGCGCUCUUGAAUACCUGCGUUCUGUAGCGCUAGUUCUCUUCAAGAUUUGCUUAGUGUCAUUUCAUUUCGGUUUCUUUUCUCGCCAUGUUUUUCUGUCGGAAUUACGGUUCGUUUUGGUUCUAUGUACUCUCUAAAAUGUUAUCGUUUUUCAUUUGUCUACUAAUUUUCGUGCAUUUGUUACUACUGAGUUUCUUAAUAUCUGACUGGCCUCCGCCCACGGGCUCUGCAGAGCAUAAAUACUCAGGCUGAUGGUAGUGCAGAGACUCUCCCUCCUUGAUCAGCGCAAACGUUGGUCUGAGGCUUGAGGGAUGGAGCAACAUUUUCUUGGCUGUGUGAAGCGGGCUUGGGAUUCCGCAGAGGUGGCGCCAGAGCCCCAGCCUCCACCUAUUGUGAGUUCAGAAGAUCGUGGGCCGUGGCCUCUUCCUUUGUAUCCAGUACUAGGAGAGUACUCACUGGACAGCUGUGAUUUGGGACUGCUUUCCAGCCCUUGCUGGCGGCUGCCCGGAGUCUACUGGCAAAACGGACUCUCUCCUGGAGUCCAGAGCACCUUGGAACCAAGUACAGCGAAGCCCACUGAGUUCAGUUGGCCGGGGACACAGAAGCAGCAAGAGGCACCCGUAGAAGAGGUGGGGCAGGCAGAGGAACCCGACAGACUCAGGCUCCAGCAGCUUCCCUGGAGCAGUCCUCUCCAUCCCUGGGACAGACAGCAGGACACCGAGGUCUGUGACAGCGGGUGCCUUUUGGAACGCCGCCAUCCUCCUGCCCUCCAGCCGUGGCGCCACCUCCCGGGUUUCUCAGACUGCCUGGAGUGGAUUCUUCGCGUUGGUUUUGCCGCGUUCUCUGUACUCUGGGCGUGCUGUUCACGGAUCUGUGGAGCUAAGCAGCCUUAGAUAGCAGCAGAAGGCUUUUUGGAUUCUCCUCCUUGAAAAGAUUCUCAGUUACCAAACGUCUCCACCUAGAAAAUAAAAAUACAUUAAGAUGUGC